AGAAGGUGGCGAGUUUCGCGGCCAGAGGCUUACAGGUCCAGGUGGAGAGGCCGGGCUGGCCAGGGCUUCGGCCUCCGGCGUCGGGAAAUGGCGGCGGGGGGCAGGAUGGAGGACGGUUCCUUGGAUAUCACCCAGAGUAUUGAAGACGACCCACUUCUGGAUGCCCAGCUUCUCCCACACCACUCAUUACAAGCUCACUUUAGACCCCGAUUCCAUCCUCUUCCUACAGUCAUCAUAGUGAAUCUUCUGUGGUUUAUUCAUCUCGUGUUUGUUGUUUUAGCAUUUUUAACAGGUGUGCUUUGUUCUUAUCCUAAUCCAAAUGAGGACAAGUGCCCAGGAAAUUACACAAACCCAUUGAAAGUUCAGACGGUUAUAAUCCUUGGGAAAGUUAUUUUGUGGAUUCUCCAUUUACUCCUUGAAUGCUACAUCCAGUAUCACCACAGCAAAAUCAGAAACCGAGGCUAUAACUUGAUCUACCGAUCAACAAGGCAUCUCAAGAGACUUGCGUUGAUGAUACAGUCCUCUGGCAACACAGUGCUUCUCCUCAUACUGUGCAUGCAGCACUCCUUCCCAGAGCCUGGCAGAUUGUAUCUUGACCUCAUUCUGGCCAUCUUGGCACUGGAACUCAUCUGUUCCCUGAUAUGUCUCCUCAUUUACACAGUGAAAAUCCGGAGAUUUAAUAAAGCUAAACCAGAGCCUGAUAUACUUGAAGAAGAAAAAAUCUAUGCUUACCCCAGCAAUAUUACCUCGGAGACUGGAUUCAGAACUAUUUCAAGCCUAGAAGAAAUUGUUGAAAAGCAAGGAGACACCAUUGAAUACCUGAAGCGACACAAUGCGCUGCUGAGUAAGCGAUUGUUGGCUCUCACUUCCUCAGACCUGGGCUGUCAGCCAAGUAGAACGUGAGAGGCUCACGGUCAUGACAGCAAUUGCAGAGGAACCCAGAGUAAUUGAGACUGACUGACCACCUGACAAGCUGCCACGGGGAACUGCAGCUUUUGCUGAAUAGCAUUUUACAGUGUUUGUUGGAAACCUGAAUUUGGUUCUGACUUCUGUGGCUGUUUAAAAUAUAGGGCUUGUGGGUCACUUGAAAAGUACCUGUAGAAGCCCGGAUAACUUGAGGGGAAUGUCUGUUUGUACUUUUGGAAAUUAUUUAACUGCUUGGUUUAUCCUAGGAUCAGAGGCUAAACAACUCCAUAGUCAACACUUUUCCACCUGACAUUAGAACCCUGUAAUGAUUUCAUUAUGGAUAGGGGAAGUCUAACAAGACAAUCGAUUUUAAACAGGGUUUUAAUCAAAUAAGUUCUUCCCACUUUUAAGCUGAUGAAAGAAGUCAUUAUUUCUUGUGAAUAUUUUUUCCUGGAGAGCCUUAUCAUGUAUUUUAUAUGCUUAUGUGGUGUUGGAUGACAUCAUGGACCAUAUAGCUUUUAUAGAGAAUUUUUCUCACCAUAGGACUGAGGUCUCACCAGGUGAUCUACUAUGCAAAUUCCUACAGUUUUCUAUUCUUAAGAAAUAAGGGCUGGGCACGGCGGAUCAUGAGGUCAGGAAAUUGAGACCAUCCUGGCUAACACGGUGAAACCCUGUCUCUACUAAAAAUACAAAAAAAAUUAGCCGAGCAUGGUGGCGGGCACCUGUAGUCCCAGCCACCUGGGAGGCUGAGGCAGGAGAAUGGUGUGGACCCAGGAGGCGGAGCUUGCAGUGAGCCGAGAUCACGCCACUGCACUCCAGCCUGGGCGACAGAGCGAGACUCCGUCUCAAAAAAACAAAAAAGAAAAAGAAAAGAAAUAAGAUAUGAUGAUUGAUUACUUGGACCAGUGUUAGACCGACCUGUGUUAGACGAACCUGUGUUGCCUAUUAUAUUGGCAGCACCUUCCAUUAGCAAUAGCUGAAAAAUUCAGAGAAGAAUUUAGAACUUUCACUUUAUUUUUGCCAUUCUUCAAGAAGUUGCUGUAUAUUUCAGUCUGGUUAUACCUUCAAUUGAUCAAUAACUUCAAUUAUAGGAAAGGCAUCUUCUAUAAUUUUAAAUUACUGUAAAAAAAAGAUACCUUUUAAAGCCUUGGAUUAUACUUAAAAAUUGUAAUGGAAGAAAUGCAUAUUAAGUUAUAUGCAGAUAUUAAACAUAUCUGAUUCUGAAGAUAAAACUGAAGUAUUUUUCAGAGCAAAUGGCAUUAUUUCUCCAUUUUUCCUAGUAUGCCCCUUUAAUUUGUCAGUUUGCUGUUAGCACUGUUAUAUGCUGCCUUAGAAAGACUUUUGGUUGAAGGCUGAAUAUGAGGGGAGGGGAUAUUUAUGACUGUGUUAAUCUUUUUUGAUCAUUAGCUGAAUAUUCAAUAUUUGAUAUGUAACCAUAUAGGGAUGUGUUCGAUAUAACUAUAUAGGCAAGGGAUAUAUUGAUUUGGCCACAUCUAUUUGACUUAUGGAGGGCAAAUACCUGUUUCUUUUAGAUACAGCCAUUGCCGGGGCAUUCUAAAAGUUUUCUACUAAGAUAAAGAUGAUUGUGUAUGGCUGGGAGCAGUUGCUCAUGCCUGUAAUCUUAGUACUUUGGGAGGCUGAGGCAGGAGGAUCACUCAAGGCCAGGAGUUUGAGACCAGCCUGGGCAACAAUGAGACACUGUCUCUCAAAAAAAAAAAAAAAAGAUCGUGUGUCACCUGCACACAACAUUCACAAACUAAAGCCAAAUUGUAUUUUUAAAAUUUCCUUUCUCCCUUCCGUUUUUUUUUGUUUUUUGGGGGUUUUUUUUUUUGUUGUUGUUUUUGAGACAGAGUCUCACCCUGUCGCCCAGGCUGGAGUGCAAUGGCGCCUUUCUUUCUUUCUUUUUUUUUCAGACGGAGUCUCGCUCUGUUGCCCAGGCUGGAGCGCAGUAGCAUGAUCUCGGCUCACUGCAACCUCCGCCUCCCGGGAUUAAGAAAUUCUCCUACCUCAGCCUGCUGAGUAGCUGGGAUUACAGGCACAUGCCACCAUGCCUGGCUAAUUUUUGUAUUUUUAGUACAGGCGGGGUUUCACCAUGCUGGCCAGGCUGGUCUCAAACUCCUGACCUUUUGAUCCGCCCUCCUUGGCCUCCCAAAGUGUUGGGAUUACAGGCAUGAGCCACUGUGCCCGGCCUUCCUUUCUUUUUAAUAAGUGUAUGUAUCUCAAAGCCAUUGCCUUCUCUAGAAAUCUGUUUCUCUGUUCUGGAAGAGCCUAUAAACUUUGCCUUCAGUUGUUUUUCUUUUCAAAAGGGAACACCAGUGGUAGAUGAUUAACUCUUAUUUAUUUUUAAAAUUUAAUUUGGAUCUAUAGUCAGUAUCUGAGAUUUAUAGGAUGAACUUUGGUUUACAAGGAACAGUGUAGUUAAAAAGUUAGGGUGCCUAUGUUCUUAUGUAAUCAUCAACAUGUUUGUUGUAUAAUCAUCAACAUUUUUCUGAAUGCAAUGAUGAACAUUUCAAACAAUAAAUGAAAAUGAAACUAAGUAUCAGAAGUAGCAAAACAGCUGAUGCAGUGGCUUACGCCUGUAAUCCCAGCACUUCGGGAGGCUGAGGCAGGUGGAUCACCUGAGGUUAGGAGCUCAAGACCAGCCUGGCCAACAUAGUAAAACCCCAUCUUUACUAAAAAUACAAAAUAAGCCAGGCAUGGUGGCACGCAUCUGUAAUCCCAGCUACUCAGGAGGCUGAGGCAGGAGAAUCGCUUGAACACAGGAGGCAGAGGUUGCAGUGAGCUGAAAUUGCACCACUGCAUUCCAGCUUGGGCAACAGAGCUAGACUCGAUCUCAAAAAAAAAAGAAGUAACAAAACAGAAAAAUGAACAAAACAAUUUAAAUGUUAAACAUUCUAUUCACCAGGCUGGUAAUUGUGCUAGCACUGAGGAUACAAAAAUUAAAGACUCUGGUUGGCAGCUUACAUUCUAAAGAGAGCGAGGAAUAGAUUUCCAGACUCUGUGCUAAGUGCAGUAAUGACAGUAGGCCCAACAUGCUGUAGGAGCUCCACGUCAGGGGGUACCCUGGGGGCAGGAGGGUAGAGGGUUUUAAGAAUGUCAGACAGAACAAUGAGUAAAGUAGGAAGGCAAAUAGCUACAAAAUAUCACAAGCACUGUGUAUAGCUGGAACCAAAAGUGUGAGGCAGGACCUGGGUGGAGAGGUAGACAGGGUCAGAGCUUGGAGGGCCUUGAUACUAUGCUGGAAGACUGCACUUUAUCUUGUUGAUAAUGGGAUCCUCUGAAGCAUUUCAAGCAAGGAAGUGACAAUGUCAGUUUUAGUUUCAGCAGGAUCAGAUGGUAGUUCAAUAUGGAGGAAAUAUGUGUGGCAGAAAGAUAUGGCCCUGAACUAGGGCAGGUAUAGUAAACCUUUUAUUAUAAGUAUGUAUGUGUAUAGGUAUAUAGAUAGAUAUAGGUAUAUAUGUAUGUAUAUGUAUUCCAAAUGACAACAGUAUCAUGACUUAUUAUAAAGUUAAAAGCUCAUUUUUUAAAAAAUGGCAAUAUGGAAAAAUAUAAAGCAAAACAAUUAUUUGAAAUCUCACUACCAAGGGAUUAUACCAAUGUACACUUUUUUUGUUUUGUUUUUUUUUUUAGUCUCAUCUGUCUCCCAGGCUGGAGUGCAGUGGUGUGAUCUGGGCUCACUGCAACCUCCUUCUACCGGGUUCAAGCAAUUCUCCUGCCUCAGCCUCCCAAGUAGCUAGUACUACAGAUGCAUGCCACUAUUUUUUAGUACAAAAAUAUUAAAAAUUUGGGUCGGGUGUGGUAGCUUACGCCUGUAAUACCAGCACUUUGGGAGGCCAAGGUGGGUGGAUCACAAGGUCAGGAGUUAGAGACCAGCCUGGCCAAGAUGGUGAAACCCCAUCUCUACUAAGAAUACAAAUAUCAGCCAGGUGUGGUGCAGGGUGCCUGUAAUCCCAGCUACUCUGGAGGCUAAGGCAGGAGAAUUGCUUGAACCCAGCAGGUGGAGGUUGCAGUGAGGCAAGAUCACGCCACUGUACUCUAGCCUGGGCCACAGAGCAGGCUCCAUCUCAAAAAAAAAAAAAAAUACUAAAAAUUUUGUAUUUCGGCUGGGCACGGUGGCUCACACCUGUAAUCUCAGCACUUUGGGAGGCCGAGGCGGACAGAUCACGAGGUCAGCAGAUCGAGGCCAUCCUGGCCAGCAUGGUGAAACCCUAUCUCUACAAAAAAUACAAAAAUAUUAGCAACAUUAGCUGGGUGUGGUGGUGCGCGCCUGUAAUCCCAGCUACUCAGGAGGCUGAGGCAGGAGAAUUGCUUGAGCCUGGGAGGCAGAGAUUGCAGUGAACCAAGAUGGUGCCACUGCACUCCAGCCUGGCGACAGAGCAGAGCGAGACUCCAUCACAAAAAAAAAAAAAGAAAGAAAAGAAAAAAAAUUGUAUUUCUAGUAGAGACGGGGAUUCACCAUGUUGGCCAGGCUGAUCUUGAAUUCCUUACCUCAGGUGAUCCACCUGCUUUGGCCUCCCAAAAUGCUGGGAUUAUAGGCAUGAGCCAGCUCACCUGGUCUCCAUACCCUUACCAAUAGUGGGUGUUACCUUAUUUAAGUCUUGACCCAUCUGAUGAGUGUGUCAUUGUUUCAAAUUGUAUUUCUUUGGAUACUAAUGAAGUGUUAAACAUUUUUUCCAAAUUAUAUGGUCUUUUAUAAAUCUUUUAUGACAUGUAUAUUCAAGUCCUUUGCUUAUUAUUGUCCCAGGAUAUUCUUUUUCUUAACAACUAGAAUCUUCUGGUUGGGCGUGGUGGCUCCCGCCUGUAAUCCCAGCACUUUGGGAGGCCAAGGCAGGCAGAUCACUUGAGGUCAGGAGUUCGAGACCAGCCUGACCAACAUGGAGAAACCCCAUUUCUACUAAAAAUACAAAAUUAAGGCUGGGCGCAGUGGCUCACACCGGUAAUUCCAGCACUUUGGGAGGCCGAGGCAGGCGGAUCAUGAGGUCAGGAGUUCGAGACCAGCCUGACCAACAUGGAGAAACCCCGUCUCUACUAAAAAUACAAAAUAGCCAGGUGCAGUGAAGUGCACCUGUAAUCCCAGCUACUCAGGAGGCUGAGGCAGGAGAAUUGCUUGAACCCGGGAGGUGGAGGUUGCAGUGAGCCGAGAUCGCACCACUGCACUCCAGCCUGGGUGACAGAGCGAGACUCUGUCUCAAUAAAUAAAUAAAUAAAUAAAUAAAUCUUGAAUACAAAACUCACAUCUGGUAAACUCUUGAGUUCUUGAAGAAUCAAACUUUGAAUAUGUGACAAUCACAAAUUUGAGAUCUCAAAACAUUCUCUAGGUUUCCUAAGGAAAAUUGUUUCAUUCGCAAACCAGGGAAGCCUAUCUCUAAUUCUUCUCCCUUCCUCUCUAUCCAGUCUCACCUUUCACUCUACUACUCUACUGAAACUGUUCUUGGCAAGGUCACCAAUAGCUUCCUUCCACAUUGCUUAAAUUGGAGAUGAAUGCAUACGUCUCCUCUUUUAACUUAUCAGCAACACUUGGCUCAGUUGAUUGAGGGGGGGUCUGCCCCUCCACACCUGUGGGUAUUUCUCGUCAGGUGGGACGAGAGACUGAGAAAAGAAAUAAGACACAGAGACAAAGUAUAAAGAAAGAACAGUGGGCCCAGGGGACCAGCACACCCAGCAUGCGAGGACCUGCACCGGCGCCGGUCUCUUGAGUUCUGUUAGUAUUUAUUGAUCAUUAUUUUUAAUAUCUUGACGAGGGGAGUGUAGCGGGGCAACAGGUGGGGAGAAGGUCAGCAGGGAAACGUGAGCAAAGGAAUCUGUAUCAUGAAUAAGUUCAAGGAAAGGUACUGUGUCCGGAUGUGCAUGUAGGCUAGAUUUACGUUUCUCUUUACACAAACAUUUCAGUGUAGCAAAGAGUAACAGAGCAGUAUUGCUGCCAGCAUAUCUCGCCUCCAGCCACAGGGCAGUUUUCUCCUAUCUCAGAAUAGAACGAAUGGGAAUGGUCAGCUUUACACCGAGACAUUCCAUUCCCAGGGACGAGCAGGAGACAGAAGCCUUCCUCUUAUCUCAACUGCAAAGAGGCCUCCCUCUUUCACUACUCCUCCUCAGCACAGACCCUUUACAGGUGUCGGGCUGGGGGAUGGUAAGGCCUUUCCUUUCCCACGAGGCCGUAUCUCAGGCUGUCUCAGUGGGAGGAAACCUUGGACAAUACCCAGGCUUUCUUGGGCAGAGGUCCCUGCGGCUUUCCGCAGUGCAUUGUGUCCCUGGUUAAUCGAGAAUGGAGAAAGGCGAUGACUUUUACCAAGCAUACCACCUGCAAACAUAUUGUUAACAAGGCACAUCCUGCACAGCCCUAAAUCCAUUAAACUGAUCCAAUACAGCACAUGUUUCUGUGAGCACAGGGUUGGGGCUAAAGUUAUAGGUUAACAGCAUCUCAAAGCAGAAACAAUUUUUCUUAGUACAGAUCAAAAUGGAGUUUCUUAUGUCUUCUUUUUCUACAUAGACACAGUAACAAUCUGAUCUCUCUCUUUUCCCCACAGUUGAUCACUUCCUCCUUGACUCUUUAUUUCAGCUUGGCUUCCAGGACACUACAUUCUCCUCAUUUUCUUCUACUUCACUAGCUUCUUCUUUUGUCUGCUUUGCAAGUUGCUUUUUGUUGGUAUUCUCCAGGGCUCAACCCCUGGGCCUCUUGGCUUCUCCAUCAGCGUUCACUCUCUUGGUGGUCUCACACAAUCUCAUGACUUUGAUAGAAUUUAUGAGCUGAUAAUUUCCAAAUGUGAAUCUUCAGCCAGGCCUUCCUCCCUGAACUCCAGACUUAUGUGUCCAACUGCCCCUUCUAGAUCACUACUUGGGUAUAUAAAAAAACACCUCAAACAGAACAUGUCCCCAGCUGAGCUAUCUGCCACAGUCUCUUCCACCCCUGUAAUGGCAGCUCCUCUUUCUCUCAAACCCUAUAGACAGUUAAUCAGCAAAUCCUGCUGGCUUUUCCUUUAAAACAUACCCAGAGUCCAACCAAUUCUUGGCACCCCCAAUGCUACUUCCCCAGCCACUAUAAUCUUCACCUGGACUAUUAUAAUAGUCUUUCGGUUUUUUGGUUUUGUUUUUUUUUUUUGGGGGAGGGAGUCUCGCUCUGUUGCCCAGGCUGGAGUGCAGUGGCGCGAUCUGGGCUCACUGCAACCUCCGCCUCCCAGGUUCAAGUGAUUCUCUUGCUUCAGCCUCCUGAGUAGCUGGGAUUACCGGCACAUACCACCACACCCAGCUAAUUUUUUUAUAUUUUUAGUAGAAAGGGGGUUUCACCAUGUUAGCCAGGCUGGUCUUGAACUCCGGACCUCAGGUCAUCCACCCGCCUUGGCCUCCCAAAGUGCUGCAAUUACAGGCAUGAGUCACUGUGCCUGGCCCUAUUAUAAUAGUGUUUUUCUUUUUCUUUUUCUUUCUUUCUUUUUUCUUGAGAUGGAGUCUCACUCGUGUCGCACAGGCUGGAGUGCAGUGGCGCAGUCUCGGCUCACUACAACCUCCGCUGCCCAGGUUCAAGCAAUUCUCCUUCCUCAGCCUCCUGAGUAGCUGGGAUUAUAGGUGUGCUUUUUUUAUUUUUAGUAGAGACGAGGUUUCACCAUGCUGACUAGGCUGGUCUGGAACUCCUGACCUCAUGAUCCUCCCUCCUUGGCCUCCCAAAGUACUGGGAUUACAGGCAUGAGCCACCACACCUGGCCUAUAAGAGUCUUUUAAGUGAUCUUUCUGCUUCUCACUACCUCUCCACCCUGACCCCCCAGCCCCAUGCACACACACAAAAAGCAGCCAACAAUAUCCUUCUAAAACACUACUCUGAUGGUUCCCUUUUUCAUUCAGUAAAAGCCAAAGCCUGGACAGUGGCCUUCAGGGACCUAGAAAAUCUCCACUUCCCACCCCACCCCACCUCCUCUCUCCUACUCUUCCUUUGUGUACCCUGCGUCGGUCACACUGUGGCUUUUGGAUUGCUAAGCACAUUCUUACCUGAGGACCUUUGCGGUUGCUGUUCCCUCUGCCUGGAAGGAUCAACUCCCAUAUAUCUUUUUCAAGUCUUUGUUCAAAUGUCACUUGUGGCCAGGUGUGGUGGCUAACCCCUGUAAUCCCAGCACUUUGGGAGGCUGAGGUGGGUGGAUCACUUGAGGUCAGGAGUUGGGAGACCGGCCUGGCCAACACGAUGAAACCCUGUCUCUACUGAAAAUACAAAAAUUAGCCAGGCGUGGUGGCACGUGUCUGUAAUCCCAGCUAUUCAGGAGGCUGAGGCAGGAGAAUCACUUGAACCUGGGAGGUGGAGGUUGCAGUGAGCCAAGAUCGCACAGCUGUACUCCAGCCUGGGUGACAAGAGUGAGAAUCCGUCCCCCCCCCAAAAAAAAAAAAUCCUCCCACUUCAGUCAGCCUCCUGAGUAGCUGGGAUUAUAGAUGUGCACCACACCACCACACGUAACUUUUAUUAUAGUAUAUUGCUAUAAUUAUUCUAUUUUGUUAUUAAUGUUGUUACUCUCUGUGCCUAAUUUAUAAAUUUAACUUUAUUGUAGUUAUGUGUGGAUAGGAAAAAAUAUAGUGUUCGUAGGGUUUAGUACUAUCUGUGGCUCCAGGCAUCACCUGAGGUCUUGCAAUGAUUCCCCUGCAGACCUGUGGCUCCAGGCAUCACCUGAGGUCUUGUAAUGUUUCCCCUGUAGAUAAGGGGAAAAUACUGCAUGUAACUUACUUGUUUACUUUGUCUGUGUCUCCUGAUAGAAUGUAAGCUCUAUCUUUUGCUUACUACUGUGUCCUUCAUACAUAGAACAGUGUCUGGCACAAAGUAGGCACUCAAUAUACGUUGAUGAAUUAAUGUCACUAACUUCAGUGAUUUCACUACUGGAAUUGUAGUAGAAAAACUAUGCUCACACAUGCUCAAAGCCUGUUCCUGUAAUCCAGCUGUAACCUGGGCUCUGUUUUCACUUUCUGUUUAUGAUGUCCUGAACUGAGAGAUUAUUUUUUUAAGGUCUUGUUUAAAAGUUUAUGUCUAGGAUACACUAAAAAAUAACAACAUAUCAGAAAUAAAAGAGAUAAGACUGCUA